GAGUCGCACGGAGGGCAACCGUCGACGGGCUUAGCGCCUCAACUGUCGUUGGUGUAUUUUUCUGGUGUCACUUCUGUGCCUUCCUUCAAAGGUGGUGCUUUGUCCCUGUGGGUCAUCUGUACUGAUUGCGCCAAGCAAAGCAUUUGUUCUCCAAAUGUCAACUGUCAAGGAGCAGCUAAUUGAGAAGCUAAUUGAGGAUGAUGAAAACUCCCAGUGUAAAAUUACUAUUGUUGGAACUGGUGCCGUAGGCAUGGCUUGUGCUAUUAGUAUCUUACUGAAGGAUUUGGCUGAUGAACUUGCCCUUGUUGAUGUUGCAUUGGACAAACUGAAGGGAGAAAUGAUGGAUCUUCAGCAUGGCAGUCUUUUCUUUAGUACUUCAAAGAUUACUUCUGGAAAAGAUUACAGUGUAUCUGCAAACUCCAGAAUAGUUAUUGUCACAGCAGGUGCAAGGCAGCAGGAGGGAGAAACUCGCCUUGCCCUGGUCCAACGUAAUGUGGCUAUAAUGAAAUCAAUCAUUCCUGCCAUAGUCCAUUAUAGUCCUGAUUGUAAAAUUCUUGUUGUUUCAAAUCCAGUGGAUAUUUUGACAUAUAUAGUCUGGAAGAUAAGUGGCUUACCUGUAACUCGUGUAAUUGGAAGUGGUUGUAAUCUAGACUCUGCCCGUUUCCGUUACCUAAUUGGAGAAAAGUUGGGUGUCCACCCCACAAGCUGCCAUGGUUGGAUUAUUGGAGAACAUGGUGAUUCUAGUGUGCCCUUAUGGAGUGGGGUGAAUGUUGCUGGUGUUGCUCUGAAGACUCUGGACCCUAAAUUAGGAACGGAUUCAGAUAAGGAACACUGGAAAAAUAUCCAUAAACAAGUUAUUCAAAGUGCCUAUGAAAUUAUCAAGCUGAAGGGGUAUACCUCUUGGGCUAUUGGACUGUCUGUGAUGGAUUUGGUAGGAUCCAUUUUGAAAAAUCUUAGGAGAGUGCACCCAGUUUCCACCAUGGUUAAGGGAUUAUAUGGAAUAAAAGAAGAACUCUUUCUCAGUAUCCCUUGUGUCUUGGGGCGGAAUGGUGUCUCAGAUGUUGUGAAAAUUAACUUGAAUUCUGAGGAGGAGGCCCUUUUCAAGAAGAGUGCAGAAACACUUUGGAAUAUUCAAAAGGAUCUAAUAUUUUAAAUUAAAGCCUUCUAAUGUUCCACUGUUUGGAGAACAGAAGAUAGCAGGCUGUGUAUUUUAAAUUUUGAAAGUAUUUUCAUUUGAUCUUUAAAAAAUAAAAACAAAUUGGAGACCUGUGACAUAACUCUAGUCUCUCAAGAUUAGAACGAGCAAAUGGUAAAGAGAUUUUCCUCUUUAAGAAUCAUUUAUAGCUCUAUUCUAAUGAUACCCAAUCUGUACAGGUGUAAGUUAUACUUCUGAGGUAUGUCACAUAUGUUAGAGUGCCUUCAGAUGUAGUAGAAUAUGUAUAAUCACUAUAAUACAGAGCUUUGAUUCUUUUCACAAACCAAGCCCUUUUUCUAGUAUUACAAUUUUAUCUUGUACUUUCAUCCGUUAGAGUACCAGCAUAUUCACUUCAUUACAUUAGCGUCAUAUGUUUAUGUAUAAUCAUUAUAAAUGUGGCCGGGCACUGCAGCCUGGGUGAAAGAGUGAGGCUCUGUCUCAAAAAAAAUCAUUAUAAAUGCUUAUUUUUAAGACCAUAUAUAUCAAAAAGAAAUAAAAAGCUGAGUGCUGUGGCUCAUGGCUGUAAUCCCAGUGCUUUGGGAGGGUGAGGCAAGAGGAUCACAUGAGUCCAGGAGUUUGAGACCAGCCUUGGCAACAUAGCAACACCCCAUCUCUACAAAAAUAAAGAAAUUAGAUGUGGUGGCCUGCAUCUGUAGUCCAGCUACUUGGGAGACUGAGACCAGUAGAUAACUUGAGCCCAGGAGUUCAAGGCUAUGAUUGUGUCACUGCACUCCAGCCUGGGCCACAGAGGAAGACUCAGACUCAAAAGAAGAAGAAGAACACAGAAGAAAAGCAGAAACAAGAAGAAGAUACAGAUGUAACUUUACGAUGUAAAAAAUCUAAAUAAGAUUGUAUUCAACUCUGCAAGUAUUAUACUAGUCAUAUAAACUCAAA